GGCGAAGGCUUUGUAGAGUUCAGAAAUGAGGCUGACUAUAAGGCUGCUCUGUGUCGUCAUAAACAGUACAUGGGCAAUCGCUUUAUUCAAGUUCAUCCAAUUACUAAGAAAGGUAUGCUAGAAAAGAUAGAUAUGAUUCGAAAAAGACUGCAGAACUUCAGCUAUGACCAGAGGGAAAUGAUACUAAAUCCAGAGGGGGAUGUCAACUCUGCCAAAGUCUGUGCCCACAUAACAAAUAUUCCAUUCAGCAUUACAAAGAUGGAUGUUCUUCAGUUCCUAGAAGGAAUCCCAGUGGAUGAAAAUGCUGUACAUGUUCUUGUUGAUAACAAUGGGCAAGGUCUAGGACAGGCAUUGGUUCAGUUUAAAAAUGAAGAUGAUGCACAUGGCCCACUGCGUGACCUUGGUUCAGCUGUCCAUUUCCUGUGACCAUCUCAUUGACAAGGACAUCGGCUCCAAGUCUGACCCACUCUGCGUCCUUUUACAGGAUGUGGGAGGGGGCAGCUGGGCUGAGCUUGGCCGGACUGAACGGGUGCGGAACUGCUCAAGCCCUGAGUUCUCCAAGACUCUACAGCUUGAGUACCGCUUUGAGACAGUCCAGAAGCUACGCUUUGGAAUCUAUGACAUAGACAACAAGACGCCAGAGCUGAGGGAUGAUGACUUCCUAGGGGGUGCUGAGUGUUCCCUAGGACAGAUUGUGUCCAGCCAGGUACUGACUCUCCCCUUGAUGCUGAAGCCUGGAAAACCUGCUGGGCGGGGGACCAUCACGGUCUCAGCUCAGGAAUUAAAGGACAAUCGUGUAGUAACCAUGGAGGUAGAGGCCAGAAACCUAGAUAAGAAGGACUUCCUGGGAAAAUCAGAUCCAUUUCUGGAGUUCUUCCGCCAGGGUGAUGGGAAAUGGCACCUGGUGUACAGAUCUGAGGUCAUCAAGAACAACCUGAACCCUACAUGGAAGCGUUUCUCAGUCCCCGUUCAGCAUUUCUGUGGUGGGAACCCCAGCACACCCAUCCAGGUGCAAUGCUCCGAUUAUGACAGUGACGGGUCACAUGAUCUCAUCGGUACCUUCCACACCAGCUUGGCCCAGCUGCAGGCAGUCCCGGCUGAGUUUGAAUGCAUCCACCCUGAGAAGCAGCAGAAAAAGAAAAGCUACAAGAACUCUGGAACUAUCCGUGUCAAGAUUUGUCGGGUAGAAACAGAGUACUCCUUUCUGGACUAUGUGAUGGGAGGCUGUCAGAUCAACUUCACUGUGGGCGUGGACUUCACUGGCUCCAAUGGAGACCCCUCCUCACCUGACUCCCUACACUACCUGAGUCCAACAGGGGUCAAUGAGUACCUGAUGGCACUGUGGAGUGUGGGCAGCGUGGUUCAGGACUAUGACUCAGACAAGCUGUUCCCUGCAUUUGGAUUUGGGGCCCAGGUUCCCCCUGACUGGCAGGUCUCGCAUGAAUUUGCCUUGAAUUUCAACCCCAGUAACCCCUACUGUGCAGGCAUCCAGGGCAUUGUGGAUGCCUACCGCCAAGCCCUGCCCCAAGUUCGCCUCUAUGGCCCUACCAACUUUGCACCCAUCAUCAACCAUGUGGCCAGGUUUGCAGCCCAGGCUGCACAUCAGGGGACUGCCUCGCAAUACUUCAUGCUGUUGCUGCUGACUGAUGGUGCUGUGACGGAUGUGGAAGCCACACGUGAGGCUGUGGUGCGUGCCUCGAACCUGCCCAUGUCAGUGAUCAUUGUGGGUGUGGGUGGUGCUGACUUUGAGGCCAUGGAGCAGCUGGACGCUGAUGGUGGACCCCUGCAUACACGUUCUGGGCAGGCUGCUGCCCGCGACAUUGUGCAGUUUGUACCCUACCGCCGGUUCCAGAAUGCCCCUCGGGAGGCAUUGGCACAGACCGUGCUCGCAGAAGUGCCCACACAACUGGUCUCAUACUUCAGGGCCCAGGGUUGGGCCCCGCUCAAGCCACUUCCACCCUCAGCCAAGGAUCCUGCACAGGCCCCCCAGGCCUAGGUUCCCUUGGAGGCUGUGGCAAGUCCUCAAUCCUGUGUCCCAGAGGUCCCUCUGGGCCACAACCCAACCCUUCUCACUCUCCUCAGUGCUAGCACUUUGUAUUUUUUGAUACUUUUAUACUUGUUUCUGCUUUUGCUGCUCUUGAUCCCACCUUUGCUCCUGACAACCCUCAUUCAAUAAAGACCAGUGAAGACCAA